ACAGUAGUAAGAGUAACACUGUAGCCGCCACCGGCAAGGGGUGCGCGCUGGGGAGCGGACGCUGCAUCCCCUUUCUGCUGCAGGAACCUCUCAUCAGACCGCCUGAGGGAAGCGGCGCCCGGAGACCCGCCCCGGCCCGGUCCACAUUCUCCCCAGGAAGCCGGACUCUAUGGGGCGGGACCCUGGGGGAGCCUGAGCCGAGCCCGGAGCCAGCCCCGAACCCCUGAACCUCCAGCCAGGGGCGCCCCGGGAGCAGCCAGCCCGUGGGCGAGCCGCCCGCCCGCCGAGCAGCCAUGAGCGAGACGGUCAUCUGUUCCAGCCGGGCCACUGUGAUGCUUUAUGAUGAUGGCAACAAGCGAUGGCUCCCUGCUGGCACGGGUCCCCAGGCCUUCAGCCGCGUCCAGAUCUACCACAACCCCACGGCCAAUUCCUUUCGCGUCGUGGGCCGGAAGAUGCAGCCCGACCAGCAGGUGGUCAUCAACUGUGCCAUCGUCCGGGGUGUCAAGUAUAACCAGGCCACCCCCAACUUCCAUCAGUGGCGCGACGCUCGCCAGGUCUGGGGCCUCAACUUCGGCAGCAAGGAGGAUGCGGCCCAGUUUGCCGCCGGCAUGGCCAGUGCCCUAGAGGCGUUGGAAGGAGGUGGGCCCCCUCCACCCCCAGCACUUCCCACCUGGUCGGUCCCGAACGGCCCCUCCCCGGAGGAGGUGGAGCAGCAGAAAAGGCAGCAGCCCGGCCCGUCGGAGCACAUAGAGCGCCGGGUCUCCAAUGCAGGAGGCCCACCUGCUCCCCCCGCUGGGGGUCCACCCCCACCACCAGGACCUCCCCCUCCUCCAGGUCCCCCCCCACCCCCAGGUUUGCCCCCUUCGGGGGUCCCAGCUGCAGCGCACGGAGCAGGGGGAGGACCACCCCCUGCACCCCCUCUCCCGGCAGCACAGGGCCCUGGUGGUGGGGGAGCUGGGGCCCCAGGCCUGGCCGCAGCUAUUGCUGGAGCCAAACUCAGGAAAGUCAGCAAGCAGGAGGAGGCCUCAGGGGGGCCCACAGCCCCCAAAGCUGAGAGUGGUCGAAGCGGAGGUGGGGGACUCAUGGAAGAGAUGAACGCCAUGCUGGCCCGGAGAAGGAAAGCCACGCAAGUUGGGGAGAAAACCCCCAAGGAUGAAUCUGCCAAUCAGGAGGAGCCAGAGGCCAGAGUCCCGGCCCAGAGUGAAUCUGUGCGGAGACCCUGGGAGAAGAACAGCACAACCUUGCCAAGGAUGAAGUCGUCUUCUUCGGUGACCACUUCCGAGACCCAACCCUGCACGCCCAGCUCCAGUGAUUACUCGGACCUACAGAGGGUGAAACAGGAGCUUCUGGAAGAGGUGAAGAAGGAAUUGCAGAAAGUGAAAGAGGAAAUCAUUGAAGCCUUCGUCCAGGAGCUGAGGAAGCGGGGUUCUCCCUGACCACAGGGACCCAGAAGACCCGCUUCUCCUUUCCGCACACCCGGCCUGUCACCCUGCUUUCCCUGCCUCUACUUGACUUGGAAUUGGCUGAAGACUACACAGGAAUGCAUCGUUCCCACUCCCCAUCCCACUUGGAAAACUCCAAGGGGGUGUGGCUUCCCUGCUCACACCCACACUGGCUGCUGAUUGGCUGGGGAGGCCCCCGCCCUUUUCUCCCUUUGGUCCUUCCCCUCUGCCAUCCCCUUGGGGCCGGUCCCUCUGCUGGGGAUGCACCAAUGAACCCCACAGGAAGGGGGAAGGAAGGAGGGAAUUUCACAUUCCCUUGUUCUAGAUUCACUUUAACGCUUAAUGCCUUCAAAGUUUUGGUUUUUUUAAGAAAAAAAAAUAUAUAUAUAUUUGGGUUUUGGGGGAAAAGGGAAAUUUUUUUUUCUCUUUGGUUUUGAUAAAAUGGGAUGUGGGAGUUUUUAAAUGCUAUAGCCCUGGGCUUGCCCCAUUUGGGGCAGCUAUUUAAGGGGAGGGGAUGUCUCACCGGGCUGGGGGUGAGAUAUCCCCCCACCCCAGGGACUCCCCUUCCCUCUGGCUCCUUCCCCUUUUCUAUGAGGAAAUAAGAUGCUGUAACUUUUUGGAACCUCAGUUUUUUGAUUUUUUAUUUGGGUAGGUUUUGGGGUCCAGGCCAUUUUUUUUACCCCUUGGAGGAAAUAAGAUGAGGGAGAAAGGAGAAGGGGAGGAAACUUCUCCCCUCCCACCUUCACCUUUAGCUUCUUGAAAAUGGGCCCCUGCAGAAUAAAUCUGCCAGUUUUUAUAAA